AAAUGCGACUCCAUCUCCCCCGACCCAAGCGCGUAAUGGCCGCUGGCUAUCUUGGGGGAGCCAGCUGUUGGACUAUGCCCCACUGCCAGGAAACAGGCGCCGGAAGGUUCUCUGACAAGAUCUCGCUUUCCUAGGGCGGUGAAGGCGUUCAAAGGUCGGGAAGGGGCGCUGGGAGAAGCGGGGCAGCGCUGAGCCAUGCUCGCGAACUGUGGGUCUGUCUGUGAAGAGACCCAGUUUCGUGGGACCACGGUGGCGCCUGCGCUGGGAGGUGAGCUUGUGACAGAGCGAAAACUACAAUUCCCAGCAUUCCUGUGGUGCCAGAACUACCUUGCCCGAAAGCCUGUGCGAGAUUUACCCCGUCUUCCGCCUCCCUCCCACCGGAAAACUCUGAGGACAUGAAUAGUCGCCAGGCUUGGCGGCUCUUUCUCUCCCAAGGCAGAGGAGAUCGUUGGGUUUCAAGGCCCCGCGGGCAUUUCUCGCCGGCCCUGCGGAGAGAGUUCUUCACUACCACAACCAAGGAGGGAUAUGAUAGGCGGCCAGUGGAUAUAACUCCUUUAGAACAAAGGAAAUUAACUUUUGAUACCCAUGCAUUGGUUCAGGACUUGGAAACUCAUGGAUUUGACAAAACACAAGCAGAAACAAUUGUAUCAGCGUUAACUGCUUUAUCAAAUGUCAGCCUGGAUACUAUCUAUAAAGAGAUGGUCACUCAAGCUCAACAGGAAAUAACAGUACAACAGCUAAUGGCUCAUUUGGAUGCUAUCAGGAAAGACAUGGUCAUCCUAGAGAAAAGUGAAUUUGCAAAUCUGAGAGCAGAGAAUGAGAAAAUGAAAAUUGAAUUAGACCAAGUUAAGCAACAACUAAUGCAUGAAACCAGUCGAAUCAGAGCAGAUAAUAAACUGGAUAUCAACUUAGAAAGGAGCAGAGUAACAGAUAUGUUUACAGAUCAAGAAAAGCAACUUAUGGAAACAACUACAGAAUUUACAAAAAAGGAUACUCAAACCAAAAGUAUUAUUUCAGAGACCAGUAAUAAAAUUGACGCUGAAAUUGCUUCCUUAAAAACACUGAUGGAAUCUAACAAACUUGAGACAAUUCGUUAUCUUGCAGCUUCGGUGUUUACUUGCCUGGCAAUAGCAUUGGGAUUUUAUAGAUUCUGGAAGUAGUAUUAAUGCUCAUCCUGCUGUGGCUGUUGGCUUCUUAGAACACCAAACCGGGAGAGAUUUACUUUGAACAUUGUCAGUUGCAGCAAAAAUUUACUACACAAGAUUAUUCGAAGUGUAUACGGACUAAAAGAGGAAGUGUUUUAGAAUGAGAAGAGAUACUGUGUCUUUAUUGUGUGUGUGUGAGUGCAGGUGUGUGUCUUUAUUAUAUUGAAAAGCUGUCACUCAGACCUGGUUUGAGAUAGAAGAGCAUUUUGUCCUUUUGAUAGUUAAUAGAAAUUGAACCAGAGUUUUCUUAUGUUUGCUUGAACAGUUGUGUAAAUCAUACAGGAUUUUGUGGGUAUUGGUUGAAUAUUUGUAAACCAUUCCCUAGCCUACAUAUUUAUUACUGAAUUAACUUUCCUGAUAACCAUUGCAUAAUUACAUUUUUCUAUAAAAUGAAAGAUUAUUACAACAAAGUUGUGUGGGUUUUCAAAGUGACUUACCAUAUAGUUGGAGAUUGAUUUCUUUUUGGUAAUGAACUAAAACAAUAAAUUUUAAAAUGAUAGGCCAGGCGCGGUGGCUCACACCUGUAAUCUCAGCACUUUGGGAGGCUGAGGCGGGUGGAUCACUUGAGGUCAGGAGUUCUAGACCAGCCUGGCCAACAUGGUGAAACCCCGUCUCUGCUAAAAAUACAAAAAUUAGCCAGGCAUGGUGGCACAUGCCUGUAAUUCCAGCUACUCGGGAGGCUGAGGCAGGAGAAUCUUGCAGUGAGCCGAGAUAGCACCACUGCACUCCAGCCUGGGUGACAGAGCAAGACUCCAUUACCUAAAUAAAUAAAUGUGUGCUUUAGUGCAAAUUACAACACUUAAUAUGAAAUCUGUAGAGUUGCUAAAUAUUGAGCUCUGAUUAUUACAUGUAUUUUUUAAAUAUUUGAUACUCAAAAACCAGUUUAUCCCUGCUUCUUAAUGUAGUUUAAGUUAACCCAUCUUAAAUUUAUUACAUAAAACAAAGCUUUUCUUAAUGACUUCAAUUCAGCAAACAUUGAUAUCUAGUACCUACUCUCAAGAAACUCAUAGGAAAAUUUAAAUUCGUAUUUUGUUUUGUUAUUAGAUAUAUUUUUUCUUACAAAGUAAUAUCUAUUAGUAAAUCAUAUGUAAUUUCAAAGAAAUUUUAAAAUAUCCUUUUCAUCUUAGUUCUUCAGUCUUACCCAGAUCAAGAAGACAAGACCAGAAAGUAAACAUUUUGAGUUCAUAAUGCCUUGGUAAUAGCUAUAAAAGUUUGACAAUCAUUAUUCAAAAUAGCCUUGUCAUUUGUUUAGCUAUAAACAGGGAAUCUGCAGUAUAGAGCAGUCAAGAGAUUGGUCCAUAUGGUCCAGUGAGUGAGAGUCAGGCUUUCCAACUAUAUUUUCCUCAAAAAUCUAACUGCUGGUUUGUUUUCAAAAGAAAAACCUUGACAUUAUCCUGUUACAUUCUGAUUCAUUUUUAUCUCUAUUGCCUAAGAGAGUUCUUAGUAUAUUAUAGAUUAAUUUUCACUGAGUCAAUUAAUAAGUUACCAUAUAUAUUAAAGUCCACUGUAACAAAGUAUACUGCAUUUGUUCAGUUAACCAAUAUGACUGCCUGCUAUAUGCCAAACAGCAUGCUAGUCCCUGUGUGCACAGAGAUGAACAUGGUUUCAUUCUCAUUGAAUUGACAAUCUUAAGGAGAGAGACAUAAACAAGUAAAUUAUUGGUUUGUUAAGAUUUAAAAUAUUCUAAAAUAUUAAGAGGGAAUGCGUCUUUCCUCCAUGUGAAGGAAGCUCCAGUAGCAUAACACUGUCGUCACUCUUCAUCCCCUUAUCCACUCUGCCCUAGGUAAAGUGACUUGCCCAAUUGUAAAUCUGGAAGGAGAAACAAGGUGCAAUUAGCCCACUUCCUCCCCACUCCUGUUUGGGACCAGCCCAUCUGAAGAGACAUUCAUUCUGUUCUGCUUCUAUGGGAUCAGGCUCUGCCUCUGCAGGAUGAGGCCUGGCCCAGUAGAGCAAUGCUUGAGACAGGGUAAAUCUGUCCAGUUCUAGAGUUCAGUGAUAAGAAGCUUACUGGCCUUAAGAUGAAACCCAUAUUCUCUUGCUGAGCACAGUGGCACACAUCUAUAGUCCUAGCUGCUUGGGAGGCUGCGGCAGCAGGAUUGCUUGAGCCAAGGAGUUCAUCAAGGCUAAAGUGUACCAUGAUCAUACCUAUAAAUAGUCACUGCACUCCAGCCUGGCAACACAUGAGACCCUGUCUCCUAAAAAAAAACUUCUCCAAUAGUUUUAUCAGCAAAUAAAGGUGUUUUUUAGGCCUCUAUAUUAGUUUAUUCAUUCUUCAUCUUAGUUAUAUUCACAACCCAGAAUGGAAAGGAGGUAUGCCAUUUAUUGGACCUUCUCAAGCCCCAACAAAUAAAUAUACUUAUUCCCAGGUUAUACAGCCACUAAAUAUUAAAUAGAUCUGCGUUCUUUCUCAUUGUAGGGGUUUAGCAAACAAAGUGCUUUGUAUCCAAUAACAGAAGAAUAGAAAUAUGCAUACCAUACCCUGUCCCCAUUACUUUUAGAUCCUAUAUCCUUUCCAUGAAACUUCAUUUUGAUGGUGGUUCUGGGGUUCAGGUAAAUUUUUGUUUCAGUGAUGGAAAUAUAUGAAAUAAGGAUGAGAGGAUUGUGUUUCUAUAUGCCUUAAAACUAUACCUCUAUUCCAGCACUUGCACUUCACUAUGAAACAGCAAUUAUACGUAUCUUUUUCCUACACUAAACUACAAGUUCUCAGAAGGCCUCUAGACACAUGUGAGGUACUUGUUAAACGCCUGUGGAAUAAAUGAUACUCAUAAAUCUCAGUUGACCUUAA